GCUCACUUAGCGUAGGCUAAGUGUAUGUGGGUAACUUCAGCUAGUGUUUGGGAGUAAUAGGGACAGAGCUCCAGGAAAUGGGGGUGUUCCUGGGACAGCAUCUGAGAGAAUAGAGGUGAAGGAGGGGCAGAGGGGGAGUGAAGGGGGGAAAUAAUGAGGCCCCGGGUCAAUGAAAGAAGCUGAAGGCUGGGCCACGUGCGAGUAAGCCAGAGUCAUUUGAUGCAGGGGCGGGAAAUAGAGGCAAAGAUAGGAAAUGAGUCUGAGUGAGAGUGAGUGGGGUGAAGAAGGAAUAUGACAUGAAAGAAUUUGGGUAAUGCUAAGUAGACUGUGAGGAAUUGCGAUAAUAUGAGGCCCAGUAUGGGUGAAUAUAAGUGGCUGAAAGGCAGUGUAAGUGAAUGGAGGAACAAAAGGCAGAAUGAGAAUGAAGUUGAAAAAGCAGUCAAGCAUAAGAAUGUAUAUGUAAUAUGCCAUUUGUAAUAUGAAAUGUGGGGCACAUUCCAGUAAAUUAGGAUGGAACAGCACUUUAAGUGCAGAGAGGUGAACAAGGUACCAAGGAUGAGUGCUAUGGUUUGAAUGUGUGCCUUCCAAAAUUCAGAUGUCAGAAACUUAAUCCCCAAUGCAACAGUGUUGGGAGGUGGGGCCUUUAAUCCCCAAUGCAACAGUGUUGGGCGAUGUUGAGGCUUCUGUGUUGCGCGUUCCAGAAUCUACCACUUAGACCUUUGCUCAUAGAGCCCAGAGUUCCAGAAUGCCCCUAAUUCCGAACACCACAGGGUGAGUCUGGAGCAAGUCACCUGGGAGGGCUUACAGGUGCCAUAAUGAAGGCCUGGGGCACUGUGGUAGUGACCUUGGCCACGCUGAUGGUUGUCACUGUGGAUGCCAAGAUCUAUGAACGCUGCGAGCUGGCGGCAAGACUGGAGAGAGCAGGGCUGAACGGCUACAAGGGCUACGGCGUUGGAGACUGGCUGUGCAUGGCUCAUUAUGAGAGUGGCUUUGACACCGCCUUCGUGGACCACAAUCCUGAUGGCAGCAGUGAAUAUGGCAUUUUCCAACUGAAUUCUGCCUGGUGGUGUGACAAUGGCAUUACACCCACCAAGAACCUCUGCCACAUGGAUUGUCAUGACCUGCUCAAUCGCCAUAUUCUGGAUGACAUCAGGUGUGCCAAGCAGAUUGUGUCCUCACAGAAUGGGCUUUCUGCCUGGACUUCUUGGAGGCUACACUGUUCUGGCCAUGAUUUAUCUGAAUGGCUCAAGGGGUGUGAUAUGCAUGUGAAAAUUGAUCCAAAAAUUCAUCCAUGACUCAGAUUCGAAGAGACAGAUUUUAUCUUCCUUUCAUUUCUUUCUCUUGUGCAUUUAAUAAAGGAUGGUAUCUAUAAACAAUGCAAAA